ACAAGGCUGAGCGGGAGGAAGCGAGAGGCAUCUAAGCAGGCAGUGUUUUGCCUUCACCCCAAGUGACCAUGAGAGGUGCCACGCGAGUCUCAAUCAUGCUCCUCCUAGUAACUGUGUCUGACUGUGCUGUGAUCACAGGGGCCUGUGAGCGGGAUGUCCAGUGUGGGGCAGGCACCUGCUGUGCCAUCAGCCUGUGGCUUCGAGGGCUGCGGAUGUGCACCCCGCUGGGGCGGGAAGGCGAGGAGUGCCACCCCGGCAGCCACAAGGUCCCCUUCUUCAGGAAACGCAAGCACCACACCUGUCCUUGCUUGCCCAACCUGCUGUGCUCCAGGUUCCCGGACGGCAGGUACCGCUGCUCCAUGGACUUGAAGAACAUCAAUUUUUAGGCGCUUGCCUGGUCUCAGGAUACCCACCAUCCUUUUCCUGAGCACAGCCUGGAUUUUUAUUUCUGCCAUGAAACCCAGCUCCCAUGACUCUCCCAGUCCCUACACUGACUACCCUGAUCUCUCUUGUCUAGUACGCACAUAUGCACACAGGCAGACAUACCUCCCAUCAUGACAUGGUCCCCAGGCUGGCCUGAGGAUGUCACAGCUUGAGGCUGUGGUGUGAAAGGUGGCCAGCCUGGUUCUCUUCCCUGCUCAGGCUGCCAGAGAGGUGGUAAAUGGCAGAAAGGACAUUCCCCCUCCCCUCCCCAGGUGACCUGCUCUCUUUCCUGGGCCCUGCCCCUCUCCCCACAUGUAUCCCUCGGUCUGAAUUAGACAUUCCUGGGCACAGGCUCUUGGGUGCAUUGCUCAGAGUCCCAGGUCCUGGCCUGACCCUCAGGCCCUUCACGUGAGGUCUGUGAGGACCAAUUUGUGGGUAGUUCAUCUUCCCUCGAUUGGUUAACUCCUUAGUUUCAGACCACAGACUCAAGAUUGGCUCUUCCCAGAGGGCAGCAGACAGUCACCCCAAGGCAGGUGUAGGGAGCCCAGGGAGGCCAAUCAGCCCCCUGAAGACUCUGGUCCCAGUCAGCCUGUGGCUUGUGGCCUGUGACCUGUGACCUUCUGCCAGAAUUGUCAUGCCUCUGAGGCCCCCUCUUACCACACUUUACCAGUUAACCACUGAAGCCCCCAAUUCCCACAGCUUUUCCAUUAAAAUGCAAAUGGUGGUGGUUCAAUCUAAUCUGAUAUUGACAUAUUAGAAGGCAAUUAGGGUGUUUCCUUAAACAACUCCUUUCCAAGGAUCAGCCCUGAGAGCAGGUUGGUGACUUUGAGGAGGGCAGUCCUCUGUCCAGAUUGGGGUGGGAGCAAGGGACAGGGAGCAGGGCAGGGGCUGAAAGGGGCACUGAUUCAGACCAGGGAGGCAACUACACACCAACCUGCUGGCUUUAGAAUAAAAGCACCAACUGAACUGA